AGCUCAACCCCCAGCACAGCAGCAUCCACCAUGUCCGUCUGCUCCAGCGACCUGAGCUACAGCAGCCGCGUCUGCCUUCCUGGUUCCUGUGACUCUUGCUCCGACUCCUGGCAGGUGGACGACUGCCCAGAGAGCUGCUGCGAGCCCCCCUGCUGCGCCCCCAGCUGCUGCGCCCCGGCCCCCUGCCUGAGCCUGGUCUGCACCCCAGUGAGCCGUGUGUCCAGCCCCUGCUGCCCAGUGACCUGUGAGCCCAGCCCCUGCCAAUCAGGCUGCACCAGCUCCUGCACGCCCUCGUGCUGCCAGCAGUCUAGCUGCCAGCUGGCUUGCUGUGCCUCCUCCCCCUGCCAGCAGGCCUGCUGCGUGCCCGUCUGCUGCAAGACUGUCUGCUGCAAGCCUGUGUGCUGUGUGCCCGUCUGCUGUGGGGAUUCUUCAUGCUGCCAGCAGUCUAGCUGCCAGUCAGCUUGCUGCACCUCCUCCCCCUGCCAGCAGGCCUGCUGUGUGCCCAUCUGCUGCAAGCCUGUCUGCUCUGGGAUUUCCUCUUCGUGCUGCCAGCAGUCUAGCUGUGUGAGCUGUGUGUCCAGCCCCUGCUGCCAGGCGGUCUGUGAGCCCAGCCCCUGCCAAUCAGGCUGCAUCAGCUCCUGCACGCCCUCGUGCUGCCAGCAGUCUAGCUGCCAGCCGGCUUGCUGCACCUCCUCCUCCUGCCAGCAGGCCUGCUGCGUGCCCGUCUGCUGCAAGACUGUCUGCUGCAAGCCUGUGUGCUCUGAGGAUUCCUCUUCAUGCUGCCAGCAGUCUAGCUGCCAGCCGGCUUGCUGCACCUCCUCUCCCUGCCAGCAGGCUUGCUGUGUGCCUGUCUGCUGCAAGCCUGUGUGCUGCAAGCCUGUCUGCUCUGUGCCCAUCUGCUCUGGGGCUUCCUCUCUGUGCUGCCAGCAGUCUAGCUGCCAGCCAGCUUGCUGCACCUCCUCCCAAAGCCAGCAGGGCUGCUGCGUGCCCGUCUGCUGCAAGCCUGUGAGCUGUGUGCCUGUUUGCUCUGGGGCUUCCUCUUCAUGCUGCCAGCAAUCUAGCUGCCAGCCAGCUUGCUGCACCACCUCCUGCUGCAGACCCUCCUCCUCCGUGUCCCUCCUCUGCCGCCCCGUGUGCAGGCCCGCCUGCUGCGUGCCCGUCCCUUCCUGCUGUGCUCCCACCUCCUCCUGCCAACCCAGCUGCUGCCGCCCAGCCUCCUGCGUGUCCCUCCUCUGACGCCCCGUGUGCUCCCGCCCAGCCUGCUGAGGCCUCCGCUCAGGUCAGAAGCCCAGCUGCUGAUGGACACGCCCCCCAGUGCCAGCCAGGCUCAGGUCCCACCUGAAAGCUGAUAGUCGCGUCCUGAAUUGCUCCUGCACUUUGACCAUUUCCUGGUGUCUGCUGUUGAGCUGGACAAUGGAAGAACUGAAAGUCUAUACUCAAUGCUGCAGCCCUCUUGCGGGGGGAGGGGGGCGCUUCUAGAAAGUUCCCAUGGCAGUGGCCUCCCCUCCAUAUCUCCCACCUCUCAUGAGGGUCAGUUCAGCCUUGACCCGUGAGGUCUCUGUCCUCCUGGCUCAGAGCCGCAGAGCCUUCUUUGGACGCCCUCAAGCUGACCAAUAAAGGCCCUGAGACUGCAAUGGCGCUGA